AGAGUCACCCGGGCAGCCUCGGGACCGGUCACCGGCCGGCAACCGUCCAGCGGCCUCGACCACCGCCUCUAGCCUCCGUUCCCGGUCCUUUCUCCCGGGCCGAGAGACAGCGUCGCCGACAGGGGCUCAUUCCCCUCCGGUUCUCCUCGGUGACUCACCUCGGGCGGGCCGUUUUGUCUUUAGGGGCCGCCUUGGUGGGGCGAGGUUUCCGUGACGAAUCUCCUGGGGCCGUCCGUGCCGGCUCGGGCCGUCGUGGCGGCUCGAGCUCCUGGAACUUGCUCAGGCUCCGGAGGUCCGAGGCCCUCGAAGUUAUGCGUCGCCUCCAGGCGGUUGCGGCGGGCGCGGGCUCCUAAAGGGCGUCACACCCGGACUCCGCCGACUAGGCAACCUCCAUUCAUCUUUCCACUGCGCCUCCGGCGCCCCCGCCUUCUCCGGUCCCCUCCUCGGAGUCAUUUUUUCCUGUUCCCCCUCUGCCGCCCUUUCCUCACGCCCCGGGUGAGGCAAUUCUCUUGGAAGCGAAGGUGUCGGCUAUGAGCCGGAGCCUCCUUCCUUGAAUUUCUCCGUGGAGGACCCGCCGCGCCCCCCGGCAUGGGGGUGAACGCCGUGCACUGGUUCCGAAAGGGGCUCCGGCUCCACGACAACCCCGCCCUGAAGGAGUGCAUUCAGGGCGCCGACACCAUCCGCUGCGUCUACAUCCUGGACCCCUGGUUCGCCGGCUCCUCCAAUGUGGGCAUCAACAGGUGGCGAAUUUACAUUGACACUGAGGUUACACUCUAACUUCUUUUUCCCCAAAUGAUGAUCAUUUUCCACAAAAUGAUGGCCAGUUAUUCCAACACUACUUAUUGGAUCAUUUCCAAUUCAGUGAGAUUUUUGCUUCAGUGUCUUGAGGAUCUUGAUGCCAAUCUACGAAAAUUAAACUCCCGUCUGUUUGUGAUUCGUGGACAACCAGCAGAUGUGUUUCCCAGGCUUUUCAAGGAAUGGAACAUUACUAAACUUUCAAUUGAGUAUGAUUCUGAGCCCUUUGGAAAGGAACGAGACGCAGCUAUUAAGAAACUGGCAACUGAAGCUGGAGUAGAAGUCAUUGUAAGAAUUUCACAUACAUUAUAUGACCUAGACAAGAUCAUAGAACUCAAUGGUGGACAACCGCCUCUAACUUAUAAAAGAUUCCAGACUCUCAUCAGCAAAAUGGAACCACUAGAGAUACCAGUAGAGACAAUUACUUCAGAAGUGAUAGAAAAGUGCACAACUCCUCUGUCUGAUGACCAUGAUGAGAAAUAUGGAGUCCCUUCACUGGAAGAGCUAGGUUUUGAUACAGAUGGCUUAUCCUCUGCAGUGUGGCCAGGUGGAGAAACUGAAGCACUUACUCGUUUGGAAAGGCAUUUGGAAAGAAAAGCUUGGGUGGCAAAUUUUGAAAGACCUCGAAUGAAUGCGAAUUCUCUGCUUGCAAGCCCUACUGGACUUAGUCCUUAUCUCCGAUUUGGUUGUUUGUCAUGUCGACUGUUUUACUUCAAACUAACAGAUCUCUACAAAAAGGUAAAGAAGAACAGUUCCCCUCCCCUUUCCCUUUAUGGGCAACUGUUAUGGCGUGAAUUUUUCUAUACAGCAGCAACAAAUAAUCCACGCUUUGAUAAAAUGGAAGGAAACCCUAUCUGUGUUCAGAUUCCUUGGGAUAAAAAUCCUGAGGCUUUAGCCAAAUGGGCGGAAGGCCGGACAGGCUUUCCAUGGAUUGAUGCCAUCAUGACACAGCUUCGUCAGGAGGGUUGGAUUCAUCAUCUAGCCAGGCAUGCAGUUGCUUGCUUCCUGACACGAGGGGACCUGUGGAUUAGUUGGGAAGAAGGAAUGAAGGUAUUUGAAGAAUUAUUGCUUGAUGCAGAUUGGAGCAUAAAUGCUGGAAGUUGGAUGUGGCUGUCUUGUAGUUCCUUUUUUCAACAGUUUUUUCACUGCUAUUGCCCUGUUGGUUUUGGUAGGAGAACAGAUCCCAAUGGAGACUAUAUCAGGCGUUAUUUGCCUGUCCUAAGAGGCUUCCCUGCAAAAUAUAUCUAUGAUCCCUGGAAUGCACCAGAAGGUAUCCAAAAGGUAGCCAAAUGUUUGAUAGGAGUUAAUUAUCCUAAACCAAUGGUGAACCAUGCUGAGGCAAGCCGUUUGAAUAUCGAAAGGAUGAAACAGAUCUAUCAGCAGCUUUCACGAUAUAGAGGACUAGGUCUUCUGGCAUCAGUACCUUCUAAUCCUAAUGGGAAUGGAGGCUUCAUGGGAUAUUCUGCAGAAAAUAUCCCAGGUUGUAGCAGCAGUGGAAGUUGCUCUCAAGGGAGUGGUAUUUUACACUAUGCUCAUGGCGACAGUCAGCAAACUCACCUGUUGAAGCAAGGAAGAAGCUCCAUGGGCACUGGUCUCAGUGGUGGGAAACGUCCUAGUCAGGAAGAGGACACACAGAGUAUUGGUCCUAAAGUCCAGAGACAGAGCACUAAUUAGGUAAAUAUUUUAGAGCUGUAUUUCUUGCUUUAGAAGAGUAUAUAAUUAACAUAAAUUAAGAUAAUUUCAAAAAUGGAGCAAAUCUCUAUUUUCAAACCAGAAAAUCUUGAGGCAUUAAUUUUUAAGCAAUUUUUACAAACUCAGUUAAUUUUUGGUCAAGAGACAUGCAUCUGUACUGGAGAAAUUGUUGCACCAGUUUUAUAUUCAUCUGAACCAAUGCUCUUUAAAUUAGAGAUGUUUAUGAUUUUGUGGUCAAGUUUUUUCUUAGAAAAAGACAACUUUUUUAUUUCCUUACUAUGUAACUAUGAGUCUAAAACAAUUAAAGUGGCCUGUUUAUUUUAGUGACAUUAAUAUAAUCUUUUUAUGAACUUUCCCCUAAAUCUUUGCCUCUUAAAUGUUGAUAAAUUUCUUUUAUCUGUUAUGAUGCUUCUAAAAUCUAAAUUAUUUCCAAUUUGGGAAUAGUUCAAAAUUUUUUAAAAUGCUGGCCCUUAUUAGAAGUAUCAGAAAGCCUUGCCUGCAUUCAAUUUAAUUGGAUUUGGGAUGUCAUUUUGUGAUUUAAAUUAAUAUGAAAAAUAUUUAUACGUUGGAUUUGCCAGUUUUUAAAAAUUUUCUGUUUCUUCAGUUUCUAACACUGUUUACAUUUUUUAUUGCUUAGUUUUUUUAUGUCAACCUAAUUAGACUAUAAGUAUCUUGAAGAUAAGGUCAAUAAACACUCAUCACAUUUUUGUCAUUGAAUUAUUUGCAAUCAAGCUUUACCUAGUUUUUUUUUCCCCCUUAAAUCACAGAAAACAUUCAGGAGGAAUACUGUUGCAGCUGAAAUUGGUGGGGAGUUCAAUACUUUUCAAUUAAGUUAUUUAAAAAUAUUCUUCAUUGAUGGAAAGCAGUUACAUAUUGAAAUAUGUUGUUUCUAAUGACAUUUCUGUGGUUUUUAACUUUUUAAUGAAUUUCACAGAGGACAAUUGGUAAUUUGUAUAUAAAGAACUUGGCAAGAGAAUUUGCUUAAUGUAAAUAUAAACAGUCACAAUUAGUAUAGACCCAUCGAUAUAUUUUUGAUAAUUUUUCAUGUAUGGUAAAGUUAAAAUGACAAAUUGAUAUUCUGAUAUAAAACUCAAAGUUUUGAAGUCAGUGGGAAAAAAGGAGGUUUUUAGACUUUCUUAAAAGACGUUAAAAUUUUAGGACAGAAUUUUCUUGAUGUUGUUUGAUCUAACUUUGCACUCUUUGAUAAUAAUGUUUUAGAUAAUGUGCGUAAUCCAAAUUGGUAUUGUAGCCUCUGUUAACACAGACAGUAUAUGUUUUAAACUUUGAUGUAAACCUUUUUAGACCCAAACUUGUGGAAGUAUCAUGUGUUAAGUUCUCUGUCUCUGUUUCUUUGUUCAUUUAUUACUAAAAUGAACUUGUUAUUAAAGUAUAUGCAAAUAUGAAA